CUUCCAGUUUCCCGGCGUGCUUAGGGCGCGCCAAAUGGGAGGGGGAGACGCAAGAUGGCGGCAGCCGCGAACUCCGGCUCUAGCCUCCCGCUGUUCGACUGCCCAACCUGGUGAGUGGCGGGGCGGCCAGGGCUAGAGUGGCCCGGCCGGAGCUAGCCUGGGCUGGAAGGGCGGCUCUUUUUUUACUUUUCUGCUGCGAGCCGAACGGCUCAGAAACCCCGGAAUGGUUGAGGAAAAACUGUUUGCUGCACCGGGCCGGGCGACGUGUUGAAGAACCGAGAGCCUGGAGCCCAGGCCCAGGAACUGAAGAAACCCGGGGUUGGGGGCUCAAAGGCGCUCACUUAGGCAGCCCCUUUGAGCGAUUAGCCAGUCGCCGGAGCGCUUCGAGGCCUUGGCCCGAACUUACGCCCAACUCUUGACUGAGUGCCUGGUGCUCUCGUGGAGCAUCGCAUCUGGCCCCUUCCUGGCAGGUAAGCCCCCUCCCGGUUUACAUCUGGAUGUAGUCAAAGGAGACAAACUAAUUGAGAAACUGAUUAUUGAUGAGAAGAAGUAUUACUUAUUUGGGAGAAACCCUGAUUUGUGUGACUUUACCAUUGACCACCAGUCUUGCUCUCGGGUCCAUGCUGCACUUGUCUACCACAAGCAUCUGAAGAGAGUUUUCCUGAUAGAUCUCAACAGUACACACGGCACUUUCUUGGGUCACAUUCGGUUGGAACCUCACAAGCCUCAGCAAAUUCCCAUCGAUUCCACGGUCUCAUUUGGCGCAUCCACAAGGGCAUACACUCUGCGCGAGAAGCCUCAGACAUUGCCAUCGGCUGUGAAAGGAGAUGAGAAGAUGGGUGGAGAGGAUGAUGAACUCAAGGGCUUACUGGGGCUUCCAGAGGAGGAAACUGAGCUUGAUAACCUGACAGAGUUCAACACUGCCCACAACAAGCGGAUUUCUACCCUUACCAUUGAGGAGGGAAAUCUGGACAUUCAAAGACCAAAGAGGAAGAGGAAGAACUCACGGGUGACAUUCAGUGAGGAUGAUGAGAUCAUCAACCCAGAGGAUGUGGAUCCCUCAGUUGGUCGAUUCAGGAACAUGGUGCAAACUGCAGUGGUCCCAGUCAAGAAGAAGCGUGUGGAGGGCCCUGGCUCCCUGGGCCUGGAGGAAUCAGGGAGCAGGCGCAUGCAGAACUUUGCCUUCAGCGGAGGACUCUACGGGGGCCUGCCCCCCACACACAGUGAAGCAGGCUCCCAGCCACAUGGCAUCCAUGGGACAGCACUCAUCGGUGGCUUGCCCAUGCCAUACCCAAACCUUGCCCCUGAUGUGGACUUGACUCCUGUUGUGCCGUCAGCAGUGAACAUGAACCCUGCACCAAACCCUGCAGUCUAUAACCCUGAAGCUGUAAAUGAACCCAAGAAGAAGAAAUAUGCAAAAGAGGCUUGGCCAGGCAAGAAGCCCACACCUUCCUUGCUGAUUUGAUAUUUUUGGUCAUGGAGAAGGGUGGGAUUGGGUGGGAAUGGGGUGGAAGGGUGAUGGGGAGCUAAUGAACUAGGGAGAAAAACUUUCCAUGUGUGCGGUAUCGUCUUUCAGAAUGUCUCCUGGCAUCCUAACCAUGUAAUAUGACAAUUGGGGGUGGGGUUGAAAUAGCCCAUAAAGACCUGUCUUCACAACACUUGCAUUGUAGAGAAAGGCUUCUUAUAUCCUUUUCAAUAGACUGCCCUGGCUCUUUCCUAGGCCUUCCACUACCUCCUUUCUUUCUCCCACUUUCUAGGAUCAUUUUUAUGUAAAGUCACAUAUCCCAGGCCCUCAGGUUGAAUCCAGAGCUGUAGAGGUUACAGUAGCAUCACCAGCCUUGGGGGUCCAGAGCCUAAUUUAUAUUCACUAUCCUUCCAAGUCCCGGGUAGCAGAAGGGUUGCCAUAGAUCUCAGUUUGAUCAAAAAGAAGGCUUAGAAUUCUGCAGUUAAGCUGAGGUUUAAACUAAAAAAUGUUUCCUUGGGUCAGUGGUUUUGAGGUCCAGUAGCUAGGCUUUUCUCUUUUGUCCUUCCUGUUGGAAUGAAAACAUUUCGAUUUUCCUUCAUCUGUGACUGGUGCCAUAGACACAGGUUUAUAGUUUUAACUUACAGUAUUGUUUGAAAUUUACCUGUUUUUCUUGUCAAACCUGAGCACUCCUCCUGCUGAAGUUUCUUAUUUAAUUCCAGAGUACUGUCCUCUACUCUAAGGCAUUACUUUUAAGUGUAUUAUGAAGGCAGUUUUCAAAGGAUAUGACCAGUUGGGGUAAUUCAAAUUAAAAAGGAAAAGAUUUGUUUGGAAGUAACUGGUGUCUCUAAGAGGAAUUUUUAGAUGUCAGUUUGGAGGCUCUUUCCCCCCUCAAUUGAGAGCUCUUGUUAUUCAGAGCUCCAAGACUAGACCUGGCUAACAAACAUAGGAGACAAAGUUAGGAAACAUUGAUACAAGCUUUGUACAGAGAUUUGUACAUUUGUGUAAUAGGCCUUUUCAUGCUUUAUGUGUAGCUUUUUACCUGUAACCUUUAUUACAUUGUAAAUUAAACGUAACUUUUGUCAUUUGGGUGCAGGCUGUGAAUUUGUCUCUCAGUCACUGAUUGCCACUGCCAUCUGGAAAUGUUUGCUAAAGGCACAGUCACUGGGCUUGGGAGGCAAUGCUCCAUCCCCAUUAUAUUACAAAUAAAGAUGCCCUAAAUGAGUGUGGAAA